AGAGGCAGAGACACACGCGGAGAGGAGGAGAGGCUGAGGGAGGGAGGUGGAGAAGGACGGGAGAGGCAGAGAGAGGAGACACGCAGAGACACUCAGGAGGGGAGAGACACCGAGACGCAGAGACACUCAGGAGGGGAGAGACACCGAGACGCAGAGACACCCAGGCCGGGGAGCGCGAGGGAGCGAGGCACAGACCUGGCUCAGCGAGCGCGGGGGGCGAGCCCCGAGUCCCGAGAGCCUGGGGGCGCGCCCAGCCCGGGCGCCGACCCUCCUCCCGCUCCCGCGCCCUCCCCUCGGCGGGCACGGUAUUUUUAUCCGUGCGCGAACAGCCCUCCUCCUCCUCUCGCCGCACAGCCCGCCGCCUGCGCGGGGGAGCCCAGCACAGACCGCCGCCGGGACCCCGAGUCGCGCACCCCAGCCCCACCGCCCACCCCGCGCGCCAUGGACCCCAAGGACCGCAAGAAGAUCCAGUUCUCGGUGCCCGCGCCCCCUAGCCAGCUCGACCCCCGCCAGGUGGAGAUGAUCCGGCGCAGGAGACCAACGCCUGCCAUGCUGUUCCGGCUCUCAGAGCACUCCUCACCAGAGGAGGAAGCCUCCCCCCACCAGAGAGCCUCAGGAGAGGGGCACCAUCUCAAGUCGAAGAGACCCAACCCCUGUGCCUACACACCACCUUCGCUGAAAGCUGUGCAGCGCAUUGCUGAGUCUCACCUGCAGUCUAUCAGCAAUUUGAAUGAGAACCAGGCCUCAGAGGAGGAGGAUGAGCUGGGGGAGCUUCGGGAGCUGGGUUAUCCAAGAGAGGAAGAUGAGGAGGAAGAGGAGGAUGAUGAAGAAGAGGAAGAAGAAGAGGACAGCCAGGCUGAAGUCCUGAAGGUCAUCAGGCAGUCUGCUGGGCAAAAGACAACCUGUGGCCAGGGUCUGGAAGGGCCCUGGGAGCGCCCACCCCCUCUGGAUGAGUCCGAGAGAGAUGGAGGCUCUGAGGACCAAGUGGAAGACCCAGCACUAAGUGAGCCUGGGGAGGAACCUCAGCGCCCUUCCCCCUCUGAGCCUGGCACAUAGGCACCCAGCCUGCAUCUCCCAGGAGGAAGUGGAGGGGACAUCGCUGUUCCCCAGAAACCCACUCUAUCCUCACCCUGUUUUGUGCUCUUCCCCUCGCCUGCUAGGGCUGCGGCUUCUGACUUCUAGAAGACUAAGGCUGGUCUGUGUUUGCUUGUUUGCCCACCUUUGGCUGAUACCCAGAGAACCUGGGCACUUGCUGCCUGAUGCCCACCCCUGCCAGUCAUUCCUCCAUUCACCCAGCGGGAGGUGGGAUGUGAGACAGCCCACAUUGGAAAAUCCAGAAAACCGGGAACAGGGAUUUGCCCUUCACAAUUCUACUCCCCAGAUCCUCUCCCCUGGACACAGGAGACCCACAGGGCAGGACCCUAAGAUCUGGGGAAAGGAGGUCCUGAGAACCUUGAGGUACCCUUAGAUCCUUUUCUACCCACUUUCCUAUGGAGGAUUCCAAGUCACCACUUCUCUCACCGGCUUCUACCAGGGUCCAGGACUAAGGCGUUUUUCUCCAUAGCCUCAACAUUUUGGGAAUCUUCCCUUAAUCACCCUUGCUCCUCCUGGGUGCCUGGAAGAUGGACUGGCAGAGACCUCUUUGUUGCGUUUUGUGCUUUGAUGCCAGGAAUGCCGCCUAGUUUAUGUCCCCGGUGGGGCACACAGCGGGGGGCGCCAGGUUUUCCUUGUCCCCCAGCUGCUCUGCCCCUUUCCCCUUCUUCCCUGACUCCAGGCCUGAACCCCUCCCGUGCUGUAAUAAAUCUUUGUAAAUAA